GGCCUCCGUUUGCGCCGGGUCUGUGCUGGCCGCGCGCCUGGCGCUCCACGCUGAGCCUCUCCGUGCAAUGAUUAACCCGGCGGGGCGGCCGGCGCGGGACCCGAGACGGAGGCGCGGGGCCGGGGCGGGACCCCGCAGGACCGCUCGGCUUCCUGCUCUCGCCGGAGUUUCCGCGUAGAGGGCGCAUCGCCGGCCCGGGGCCCUUGGUGCGGCGUGGCGCAGGGCGCGGCGUGGGGCGCGCGUGGGCGCGGCGCAGGCGGCCCGGGUCACCAUGAGGACUCUCCGCAGGUUGAAGUUCAUGAGUUCGCCCAGCCUCAGUGACCUGGGCAAGAGAGAGCCGGCCGCCGCCGCGGACGAGCGGGGCACGCAGCAGCGCCGGGCCUGCGCCAACGCCACCUGGAACAGCAUCCACAACGGGGUGAUCGCCGUCUUCCAGCGCAAGGGGCUGCCCGACCAGGAGCUCUUCAGCCUCAACGAGGGCGUCCGGCAGCUGUUGAAGACAGAGCUGGGGUCCUUCUUCACGGAGUACCUGCAGAACCAGCUGCUGACAAAAGGCAUGGUGAUCCUUCGGGACAAGAUUCGCUUCUAUGAGGAGCUGCAGAGAGACAAGGCGGCGGCGGCUGCUGUGCUGGGUGCAGUGAGGAAGAGGCCCUCGGUGGUGCCCAUGGCUGGCCAGGAUCCUGCGCUGAGCACGAGUCACCCGUUCUACGACGUGGCCAGACAUGGCAUUCUGCAGGUGGCAGGGGAUGACCGCUUUGGAAGACGUGUUGUCACGUUCAGCUGCUGCCGGAUGCCACCCUCCCACGAGCUGGACCACCAGCGGCUGCUGGAGUAUUUGAAGUACACACUGGACCAAUACGUUGAGAACGAUUAUACCAUCGUCUAUUUCCACUACGGGCUGAACAGCCGGAACAAGCCUUCCCUGGGCUGGCUCCAGAGCGCAUACAAGGAGUUCGAUAGGAAGUACAAGAAGAACUUGAAGGCCCUCUACGUGGUGCACCCCACCAGCUUCAUCAAGGUCCUGUGGAACAUCUUGAAGCCCCUCAUCAGUCACAAGUUUGGGAAGAAAGUCAUCUAUUUCAACUACCUGAGUGAGCUCCACGAACACCUUAAAUACGACCAGCUGGUCAUCCCUCCCGAAGUUUUGCGGUACGAUGAGAAGCUCCAGAGCCUGCACGAGGGCCGGACGCCGCCUCCCACCAAGACACCACCGCCGCGGCCCCCGCUGCCCACACAGCAGUUUGGCGUCAGUCUGCAAUACCUCAAAGACAAAAAUCAAGGCGAACUCAUCCCCCCUGUGCUGAGGUUCACAGUGACGUACCUGAGAGAGAAAGGCCUGCGCACCGAGGGCCUGUUCCGGAGAUCCGCCAGCGUGCAGACCGUCCGCGAGAUCCAGAGGCUCUACAACCAAGGGAAGCCCGUGAACUUUGACGACUACGGGGACAUUCACAUCCCUGCCGUGAUCCUGAAGACCUUCCUGCGAGAGCUGCCCCAGCCGCUUCUGACCUUCCAGGCCUACGAGCAGAUUCUCGGGAUCACCUGUGUGGAGAGCAGCCUGCGUGUCACUGGCUGCCGCCAGAUCUUACGGAGCCUCCCAGAGCACAACUACGUCGUCCUCCGCUACCUCAUGGGCUUCCUGCAUGCGGUGUCCCGGGAGAGCAUCUUCAACAAAAUGAACAGCUCUAACCUGGCCUGUGUCUUCGGGCUGAAUUUGAUCUGGCCAUCCCAGGGGGUCUCCUCCCUGAGUGCCCUUGUGCCCCUGAACAUGUUCACUGAACUGCUGAUCGAGUACUAUGAAAAGAUCUUCAGCACCCCGGAGGCACCUGGGGAGCACGGCCUGGCACCAUGGGAACAGGGGAGCAGGGCAGCCCCUUUGCAGGAGGCUGUGCCACGGACACAAGCCACGGGCCUCACCAAGCCUACCCUACCUCCGAGUCCCCUGAUGGCAGCCAGAAGACGUCUCUAGUGUUGCGAACACUCUGUAUAUUUCGAGCUACCUCCCACACCUGUCUGUGCACUUGUAUGUUUUGUAAACUUGGCAUCUGUAAAAAUAACCAGCCAUUAGAUGAAUUCAGAACCUUCUAAUGAAAACUCCAUGCCUCUGGUCCUUGGACUCUUGUCCAUGGUUCCUGAGCUGUGGACCGGGAUAGAAUAA